AGGGCCGGGCUUCGUGCGGUGGGGCUCGCUCGCGCGGCAGCGGUGGCCGAGGCCUCUUGGUUCUGCGGCACGUGACGGUCGGGCCGCCUCCGCCUCUCUCUUUACUGCGGCGCGGGGCAAGGUGUGCGGGCGGGAAGGGGCACGGGCACCCCCGCGGUCCCCGGGAGGCUAGAGCGGAGACUGGACCCUAGUUCCCUGAAGAGAAAGGGGAAUGUACCAGAAGGAGAACACGCAGUGGUUGAGAAACUUAGCAGUUACAGCACCUAUUCUGGAGGCGAGUAAUCCAGUUGGAGAGGGACAGGGCGUUAAAAGCAGGAAAGCCCCCGAAAGCUCAUCUAAGUGCAUCUCUUUCCACACCGGAGGCCUGGAGAUCAUGGAAGGGAAGUGGUUGCUGUGUAUGUUACUGGUGCUUGGAACUGCUAUUGUUGAGGCUCAUGAUGGACAUGAUGAUGAUGUGAUUGAUAUUGAGGAUGACCUUGACGAUGUCAUUGAAGAGGUAGAAGACUCAAAACCAGAUACCACUGCUCCUCCUUCAUCUCCCAAGGUUACUUACAAAGCUCCAGUUCCAACAGGGGAAGUAUAUUUUGCUGAUUCUUUUGACAGAGGAACUCUGUCAGGGUGGAUUUUAUCCAAAGCCAAGAAAGACGAUACCGAUGAUGAAAUUGCCAAAUAUGAUGGAAAGUGGGAGGUAGAGGAAAUGAAGGAGUCAAAGCUUCCAGGUGAUAAAGGACUUGUGUUGAUGUCUCGGGCCAAGCAUCAUGCCAUCUCUGCUAAACUGAACAAGCCCUUCCUGUUUGACACCAAGCCUCUCAUUGUUCAGUAUGAGGUUAAUUUCCAAAAUGGAAUAGAAUGUGGUGGUGCCUAUGUGAAACUGCUUUCUAAAACACCAGAACUCAACCUGGAUCAGUUCCAUGACAAGACCCCUUAUACGAUUAUGUUUGGUCCAGAUAAAUGUGGAGAGGACUAUAAACUGCACUUCAUCUUCCGACACAAAAACCCCAAAACGGGUAUCUAUGAAGAAAAACAUGCUAAGAGGCCAGAUGCAGAUCUGAAGACCUAUUUUACUGAUAAGAAAACACAUCUUUACACACUAAUCUUGAAUCCAGAUAAUAGUUUUGAAAUACUGGUUGACCAAUCUGUGGUGAAUAGUGGAAAUCUGCUCAAUGACAUGACUCCUCCUGUAAAUCCUUCACGUGAAAUUGAGGACCCAGAAGACCGGAAGCCCGAGGAUUGGGAUGAAAGACCAAAAAUCCCAGAUCCAGAAGCUGUCAAGCCAGAUGACUGGGAUGAAGAUGCCCCUGCUAAGAUUCCAGAUGAAGAGGCCACAAAACCCGAAGGCUGGUUAGAUGAUGAGCCUGAGUACGUACCUGAUCCAGACGCAGAGAAACCUGAGGAUUGGGAUGAAGACAUGGAUGGAGAAUGGGAGGCUCCUCAGAUUGCCAACCCUAGAUGUGAGUCAGCUCCUGGAUGUGGUGUCUGGCAGCGACCUGUGAUUGACAACCCCAAUUAUAAAGGCAAAUGGAAGCCUCCUAUGAUUGACAAUCCCAGUUACCAGGGAAUCUGGAAACCCAGGAAAAUACCAAAUCCAGAUUUCUUUGAAGAUCUGGAACCUUUCAGAAUGACUCCUUUUAGUGCUAUUGGUUUGGAGCUGUGGUCCAUGACCUCUGACAUUUUUUUUGACAACUUUAUCAUUUGUGCUGAUCGAAGAAUAGUUGAUGAUUGGGCCAAUGAUGGAUGGGGCCUGAAGAAAGCUGCUGAUGGGGCUGCUGAGCCAGGCGUUGUGGGGCAGAUGAUCGAGGCAGCUGAAGAGCGCCCGUGGCUGUGGGUAGUCUAUAUUCUAACUGUAGCCCUUCCUGUGUUCCUGGUUAUCCUCUUCUGCUGUUCUGGAAAGAAACAGACCAGUGGUAUGGAGUAUAAGAAAACUGAUGCACCUCAACCGGAUGUGAAGGAAGAGGAAGAAGAGAAGGAAGAGGAAAAGGACAAGGGAGAUGAGGAGGAGGAAGGAGAAGAGAAACUUGAAGAGAAACAGAAAAGUGAUGCUGAAGAAGAUGGUGGCACUGUCAGUCAAGAGGAGGAAGACAGAAAACCUAAAGCAGAGGAGGAUGAAAUUUUGAACAGAUCACCAAGAAACAGAAAGCCACGAAGAGAGUGAAACAAUCUUAAGAGCUUGAUCUGUGAUUUCUUCUCCCUCCUCCCCUGCAAGAGUGGUCCUAGGAGAGGACCUGGCACACCUUAGGUUGACAUUCAGAAAACUUCAAGACAUCACCAUCAGCAGGCUCCAGUUGAACACUAGUCUGUGUAACUUUAAACAUCUAGCAGUAAAUACUUGCAGUUGUGAUAUAAAGGACCCUGUUUCUGUAGAAAAGAAAACAUUUAACAUAAUGGUUGUGAAAUGUAACAUGAAGCAAACUAACUUUUUUUUUUUUAACAUCUUUGUUUUUAAAAUAGAAUGAUAGAACUUUGCCAGUCUUUAAGAUCUUGGCUUAAUUUAAUGUAUUAAUCUGUUUGUGCAAACAUAAUACCACCAUUUAAAAAUGUUAGGGAGAUGAGUUGCAGUUUUUAUAAUAGAUUUUUUUUAAAGUUUGGUAUUGUAAAACAUUCACACCUCUGUCCCUCAAAAUUGAUAAUUACGUUUAAAGUGCAGUCAUUUGUGGUUAGAAUCUUGUUUUGUUUGCUUCCAUUAUUGAGUUCCUCCUAAGGAAAUUGAGGAGAGGGACUGAAUAGAAGCCCAAAUUCAUAUAAAAGUUGCGUUUAAGUUGUAUUAAAAAUAGAUAUAUAAGAAAAAAUUCUUUCACUUGAUGUUUGUUAGACCAGAAAGUGUGUGUGUUCUGUAGCUCAGUUCCCAGACAGCUUUUUAGGUAGUGGAGGAGGUGGCUUCAUGUGGCACUUGGGCAUUUAUAUUCCACUUGGGAGGGUCAGGCUGUGGCCUUCUGGAGCAGGUGGCUUGUUAAGGAAUGCUAGCAGGGCAUGGCACGUGAGCUCCGGAAUAGAUGUCUUCAUCACUUCUUCCACUGUGUGUUGACACUGUUUUCCUUACCUAUUUCCUCAGAUCCCCAGCUUUCUCCUCUGCUAUGCAUUUUCUUCACAGUGCAGCUUGCAGUCCGUUGCUGAAAAUGAUUAUAAGCCCUGCAUAAUGUUAAGCUUUAUUGUGAUUACGUGUAUGUUUCUUCUUUCUUUUAAGCAGACCCAUACCUUUCCAGGGUCAAAGUACAGAAUAGAAUACAUUGAUACAAAGUACAGAAAAAUACUUUGAUUUUUAUCCAUUUCUUUUACUCUGUGUAAAGACUUGAGAAGUCUAAUUCACAGGCAAACCAAUACAGAAUUGACUGCAGUUGAACAGACUAGAAGUAUUUGUGGGAGGAGUGACAUGAAGCAUGAGUUAUCUGAUUUUUUUUGUAGCUGCUAUAUAUUUUAAGCCUUCAUUUGCAAUUCAUGUAACAGUUGUGUCAUAAAUUACACAAUAAAGCAGUCCUGUUCAAAUUUUUUUUUAACGUGGCUUGUAGAAUUUUUAAAAAAGUGAUCUUAGGUUUGUUUUUUCAUGCGGGAUGCAGAUGGGUGCUAUCAGAGCCUCUCCCACACCACUAUAGUGUAAUAAUGUUAUUAUUACUCUACACUGAAACGUAUUCAGAGUUAGAUAUUAUUUUAGCUUCAGUUGUUCUUUAGAGGCUUUCAAAUGUACCGAUGAUACUGUUUCUUGCACUGAAUAUAUAAACACUCCACAGUGUUUAUAUUGGGAAGAUAUUGGGAAGGAAAUAUAUUUGUAAAAGAUGAAGGCUGUAUCUAUUUUUUUUUCUUUUUAAAGUUUGUUCACUUAAAUUCUUUUGAGGAUGGGAUGUAUUUUUCUUGCUGUUCAGUGCUUUUUCCUUUUCAUCUGUUGUUCUGUGGUCACAGUGACCUUAGCUACAUAGCAGACUUUCCCAAAUGUAUUGAUUACAAAUAAACAGUUGUUACUUAGCAAGACCUGAAAAUAUGUCUGCAGGUUUCUCCUUGAAGCAAAUGUGUGGGAUCAUUGCAUUUCCAGAAAUCUGCCUCCUUCACCCUCCGUUGACAGUAUAUGUCAUGCCUCACUUUCUUCUAGCUGAGCUUUAAAUCAUUAGAGCUUAAAUUGUCAGAUCGUUCAUUGCCUUUCCAGGGUUAUUUAGUAAAGUUUGUUGAAAACAAAAACGCCUUUUCUUGGUUCUUUUUUCAGUUAUUUUGAAGGUCCAGCAUCCUGAUUAAAUGUCUGACACAUUAAUGAAUGACCAGCAGCAGCUUUCAGCUCUUAAAAAGACACUUAUAUUUUGAUUUUACAUGCUGGUUACCUGUUCCAUUGUUGUCAAAUGCCCACUCUCCAUCAGAUGUGUUCCUCCAUUUUCUUAUCCACAAAGUACUCCUCACUUUUCAAUUUGUCAUGUUACUAAAUGGUGUUACAUUAAAGCCCUGUGUUAAGUGUCUGCUUUUGACUGAAUUUCUUCAUAGUAACCUUCAGUGUGUGUGUGUGACUAUGUUCAAUUAGUGGGUUGAUCUUCGUAUAAUUGGCCACUAUGUGAGAGUUCACUACUAGGCAGAAACUAUUAUGGACAGUGAAAUAAUGACUUUUAUCUCACCACGUGAGUUUGAUGCAGUCUUUUCUGUCUAGCCCUUGCCUCUUCCUGCCCAUGUGAUUGCGGUGCAGUAGUUUCUGUUGUAUAAUAGUGUGGACAGCAGCUCAGAAAAGGAGGGAAUGCUACUGAUAAUUUGUAGAUAAUAUUCUUUAAGACUUAGGGGAACCAUUGAACUUUGAAAUUUUUAUUAGAAAAUUAUUUGUUCAGAAUCAGACUCCAUUAUUUUACAUAUACUUAAAUACUUUAGGGGUAUUUUUGAAAGUUAGCCCAGUUUUUUAUGUGCUAUUAAAUUUUUAGAUUACAUACUAAAGAAAAGUAUGUACACAGAAUGUAGUGCUCCUAGUUACUAUUUUUUCUAUUAAGAAAUAGUUUAGUUCUGGUGUAAAAUUUGUUUGAAUGCUAAAAAAAAAAAAGCAGGACUGCAUUAUGGCACUUUUGCCUUGGUGGCCCACUUUCUCCAUUUAAAACAUUAGGAUUUGUAUUUUUCUGCUGCGUUUGUAUGAAGACAUAUUUGAUUGUUGUUUUCUCUUGAUUUUAAAAUAAAACCUCAUGAGCCCUAGUAAAAA